CCCUCACACCGAGAGUUCCUGCGCGUGGGGAGUUGGAGAGUUUGCGUGGCGGGAACGCGGCGGCAGUGAGAGCGAGCGGCGCCGGCCCUUGCGUCCGGUGCGGCGAUGCUGACCCCGGCGUUCGACCUCAGCCAGGAUCCGGACUUCCUGACUAUCGCCAUCCGCGUGCCCUACGCCCGGGUCUCCGAGUUCGACGUCUACUUCGAGGGGUCUGACUUCAAGUUCUACGCCAAGCCAUACUUUCUCAGAUUAACCCUUCCUGGAAGAAUUGUAGAAAAUGGAAGUGAGCAAGGGUCCUAUGAUGCAGAUAAAGGAAUUUUUACCAUUCGCCUGCCCAAAGAAACCCCUGGCCAGCAUUUUGAGGGGCUGAACAUGUUAACUGCUCUUCUGGCACCAAGAAAAUCCAGGACAGCAAAACCACUUGUGGAAGAAAUAGGUGCUUCUGAGAUUCCUGAGGAAGUAGUUGACGAUGAAGAGUUUGAUUGGGAAAUUGAGCAGACACCCUGUGAAGAGGUAUCAGAAAGUGCUUUGAAUCCGCAGUGCCACUAUGGAUUUGGAAACUUACGAUCAGGAGUGUUGCAACGGUUACAGGAUGAACUGAGUGAUGUUAUUGAUAUUAAGGAUCCAGAUUUCACCCCUGCAGCUGAACGAAGACAGAAGCGCCUGGCCGCUGAGCUGGCCAAGUUUGAUCCUGAUCAUUAUCUAGCUGACUUUUUUGAAGAUGAGGCGAUUGAACAGAUUUUGAAGUAUAAUCCUUGGUGGACUGACAAAUAUUCAAAAAUGAUGGCCUUUUUGGAAAAGAGUCAGGAACAAGAAAAUCAUGCUACAUUAGUGUCUUUUUCUGAAGAAGAGAAGUAUCAGCUACGAAAAUUUGUCAAUAAAUCUUAUCUGCUGGACAAGAGAGCCUGUCGUCAAGUGUGCUACAGUUUGAUUGAUAUCCUUCUGGCAUAUUGCUAUGAAACCCGUGUCACUGAAGGAGAGAAGAAUGUUGAAUCUGCAUGGAAUAUCAGGAAACUGAGUCCAACACUAUGCUGGUUUGAGACUUGGACUAACGUUCAUGAUAUCAUGGUGUCUUUUGGAAGAAGGGUGUUGUGUUACCCACUCUAUCGCCAUUUCAAGCUGGUGAUGAAGGCCUACAGGGACACUAUAAAGAUAUUGCAACUGGGUAAAAGUGCAGUUUUAAAGUGUCUCCUGGAUAUUCACAAAAUUUUUCAGGAAAAUGACCCAGCGUACAUACUGAAUGAUCUCUACAUCUCAGACUACUGUGUGUGGAUUCAGAAAGUCAAGGUAUAAGGGCCGUCUUUUUCUGAAAUGCGAGCCCUUCUUGAAAAUCUCACCUGAGGCUGUGCAUGGUGUCUCACGCCCAUAAUCCCAGCACUUUGGGAGACCAAGGUGAGCGGAUCACCUGGGGUCGAGAGUUCAAGACCAGCCUGGUCAACAUGGUGAAACCCCAUCUCUACUUAAGAAUACAAAAAUUAGCAUGGUGGCACGUGCCUGUAAUCCCAGCUACUUGGGAGGCUGAGGCACGAGAAUCGCUGGAACCUGGGAGGUAGAGGUUGCAGUGAGCCAAGAUUGCGUCACUGCACUCUAGCCUGGGUGACAGAGUGAGACUGUCUCAAAAAAAAAAAAAAGAAAAAAAAAAAGAGAAGAAAAUUGCCUUGAGUGCACACCACCAUACUUUUUACUUUAUUUGCUUCUAUAUUCUGCCUCUACUAAAAAUACAAAAUUAGCCGGGUGUAGUGGUGGGCACCUGUAAUCCCAGUUACUCAGAAGGCUGAGGCAGGAGAAUUGCUUGUUCUCUGAGUUGUGUAGCACAUCAAGUGAUGGAAUACACCUCUAAUAUCAUGGCAUGUUUGUCUUUUGUUUGGUUUGCCUGAUUUUAGUCUUGUGAUGGAUGAGAUAUUACUUUACAUCCCAGAUUUGUAAUUAUGUGGUAUACUUUAAGUGACAGAGUGAAAGGUGAAAAGUGAUGUCUCUUUUGAUGAUCAUCUCUUCUCCUGACUCUUGCCACUUUCGGUGUGUAUGUAUCCUAUAAACCCAGAGCAUUUACACCCCCAAAGAUGUUCUUUGUGGAUGUCACUUUUGACACCUUAAGAACCCAAAGACACAUUCUUUUGGCAAAGAAUAAAACACCUUCUCGCAUAUGGUAUUAAGUACCUUUGUGCCAUUCCAAAUAAGCUUGCCAGCCAAUUUAGAUUUUAUUUCUAUCCUUAGAUUAUCCUAAUGCUUCAGAAAAAUAAGGGUUUAGUUCUUACUAGAAGAAAUUGACUUCACUUUCAACUUGAUAUUUAAAAUUACAGUUGUCAGCAUUUGUCCUGUCUGCUUGUUUAAGGGACAUAACAGUUAAAAGGACUUCACUUAAUGCUGUAUAAGUUAGUGAUCUGAAUAAAACUAUUGGCAAAGGAUCUCCACUCUGUAUUAAAUACUGGAUUAAUCAUACAGGUCAAGCUUUCACAAUUCUAGUUGUGAAGCUUGUGUUCUGAAUGUGGCAGCACUACAUAUCCUUAUGUUUCAGAAGCUUUAUUGUGAUCCAUGGUUUCAGAUGCAUAUUUCAAAUCCAGAAAUUUUGCCUGGUAAGUAAGGCUUAUCAUACCUUUUUUAAAAAAUUAAAUAUUUUUUAAAUAGUAGAGGCAGGGUCUUGCUGUGUUGCUCAGGCUGGUCUCGAACUCCUGGCCUCAAGCAGUCCUCCUGCCUUGGCCUCCCAAAAGUGCUAGGAUUAUAGGCAUGAGCCACCUCGCCUGGCCUUGUACCUUUUUAUCAGAAAGAUCCAACCUUGCUCCAGGUUUGUGUGAAAACAGUUUUGCUUUGUUUUUAAACCAGAGCCACAUAGAUCUUUCCAUCUUCUGUAUAGGUCAGUGUUACUUGUUUCUGUUAAUCAUACUAUUUCAAAGUCCCCUGCCAUUUUAAGGUGGGCUCUCCUCUUGAGGCUUGGGCAUGAGAGUUAAGCCAGAUACUGACUUCGUUUUCUAUCUUUUGGGGUCUUGUUAUCCUAGGUGGAAAUGGUGGUUGUUUAAUUGUGACUGCUUUAGACUUGAGUAUCUGUUCAUCAGUCCAUUCAUUCAACAAAUAGUUUAUGAGUUCCUACUGUGUGCAGGGUUCUCUGCCAGGGGCCUGCCAAUGGUAAACAAAACUUGACUUGGCUUCUGCCCUUCUAGAAUUUGUGGUCUGAUGAGGAGAGAAGUAUUAAUCAAAUACUUGCAUACACAAAAAGUAAAAUUAAAACCUUGGAAAGUGGUGCAAAAGAAAAGAUUCAUACUGCCACGAGAGAUGGCUGACCUCGCCUGGUGAGGGGAUUAGGAGGAGAAGGAGGAUCCCCUGGGGAAAUGUUUGGUUUGAGUACUGAAGUACAAGUAGGAGUUAACCUAAAAAAGGUGGUGGACUUCAGGAAUACAUAGUAGUUCCAUCAUGUGCAAAGGCUCUGUGGCAGGAGGAGGGAAUUUUAUAUGUUUUCAAGAAAUUGCAAGAAGGUCAAGGUGGCUGUAACCUAGAGAAAGGGUAUAUGUGUUGGGGGAGGGGUCAAGAAAAGGCUGAUGAUUUAGUCAGAGCCCAGACAGUAUAGUGCCUUUUAAGUAAUGUUAAGAAUUUUUAUCCUUAUUCUAAGAGUAGCGAGAAGCCAGCGAAGGAUUUUCAGCAUAUGAUGGGAGAUGACUGGUGUAGUGUAAAGAGCUUUUUAGGCCAGUUUCAAGACUAUUAAUAAUGCCCUUAUGAGGCGUGAGUGUAGCCUGACUAGGGAAUUAGGAUUUUUAGGAACUCAAAUGGAUUUAGAGAAUGAGGAAGAAGGCAACAUGGAGGAUGAUGCCUGGGUUUGUAGCCUGCACAGCUGAAUGAAUGAUAAAACCUAAUUUUGGAAAAGGAAUCUCAGGGUUUUGGCUUUUGUUAGAGGAAUCUUUUCUAUACAGAACUUAAACUCUUUUGUGGUGAUCUGUACUUUAAUCAUAAUUCUGGAUAAUGGCCAGUUUUCUUUAUUUGCCUCUGUUAUUGUUGCCUUUAUUAUUUAAUGAACUACUGGGUUCAGUUAUCUAUGGAGGUUUGCCGUUUGUAUGUGUUUUUUGAAUGUUUGUAGAGUUUAGUUAUUUUCUUAAAAUGUUUUCUUAUGAAAUAUAAAAUACAAUAAUAUUUGAAGUGUAUACAAAUUAUGCAAAUUAAGUGUAUACAAUUACACAAAUGAAAGAAUAGUAAUGAACUGAAUAUUCAUGUAACUACCACUGAUUUCUUUUUUUUCUUUUCUUUUCUUUUCUUUUCUUUUUUUAAAGAGACAGGGUUUCUGUCACCCAGGCUGGAGUGCAGUGAUAUGAUCAUAGGUCACUGCAGCCUCAAACUCCUGAGCUCAAGUGAUCCUGCCAUCUCAUCCUCCCGAGUAGUUAGGACUACAGGCAUGCCCAGCUAAUUUUUUAUUUUUUGUAGAGAUAGAGUCUUGCUUUGUUACCCCAGGCUGGUUGAACAACUGGGCUCAAAUGAUCCUCCCAUUUCAACCUCUCAAAAGUGCUCAAAGUGGAUCGAUUAUAGGUGUGAGCCACCAUGCCUGGCCUCCAAUCUUAAGAAAUAGAAUAUCACCAAUUUCCUAGAGAUUCCCUAUGGGACCAUUCCCAAUUGUAUUAACUUCUGGUAACCACAACUCUAAAUUUUAUGUCAAUCAUUACUUUACUUUUCCAUAUAGUUUUACCAUUUGUGCAUAUAUCUCAAGUUUAGUUUUUAGCUUUGCUUUCUUUUGGACUUUAUGUAAUGGAAUCAUGCUAUAUGUAUGGUUCUUCUAUUACUUGUUUCUUUUGAUUUUAAAAAGAUUUAUCCAUGAUGAUGCAUAGAGUUGUAGAUGGUUCUUUUCUGUCCUGCAGUGUACUAUCCCAUUGUCUGAAUAUAGUGCUGUUUGUCUGUCUGUUAUUCUGUGGAACCACUAAUAAAUGGUUUCCAGUUUGGGCUAUUCAGAAAAUGCUGCUGCAGAUAUCACUAUACGUGUUUCAUGGUGUACUUGUGCAACUUUUUGGUUAAGCCCUAUACCUAGGAAUGGAAUUUCUGGGAUUAGGGACAAUGAUAUGUUAGCCUUUAAUGGGCAGUGUCAAACUGUUUUCCAAAGUGGCCAUACCAGUUUAUUUCAACUUAUACUUUAACCAGCAAUGUAUAAUAAUUUUCCUGAUUCCACCUUCAUGCCAACACUUACAUGGUUCAGAUUUUACGAUUUGACAAUCUGAAGGGGUAUGAAAUAGUUUCUGUUGUAAUUUUAAUUUGCAUUUUCCUAAUUACUAGUGAAGCUGAGCAUCUUUUCAUGUGUUUAUGAGCCAUUGGUGUUUCCUCUACUAUGAAAUGUCUGUCUAUUGUAUCCCCUGUUUUUCAAUAGGACUUCCUUUCUUUUUGAUUUAUAGGAUUCCUUCCAGUAUUCUGGAUACUAGUCCUUUAUGGGUUAAAUAUGUUGCAAAUAUUUUCUUCCAGUUUAUAGUUUAUGUUUCAGUCUCCUUGUAGUGUUUUCAUAAACAGAAGUUUUUAAUCUCAAUGCUGUAGAAUUUCUCAAUGUGUUCCUUUAUGGGUGUGCUUUUGGUUCUCGUUUAAGAAAGUUUUUAUGAUUUGGAUGUUAUAGAGAUAUUCUCCUAUAGUAUCUUCUAAAUUUUUUAUUCUUUUGCAUUUUGCAUUUAAGUCCUUAGUCCACCUGGAAUAGAUUUUUUGUAUGUUAUGCAAUAGGGGAUCCAGUUUCUUUUUUCCCAUAUGGAUAACCAUAUCCUGGCUUCAUUUAUUAAAUAGUCUAUCCUUUCCUCAUACAUCCUGCAGUGCUCACUCUUAUAAAUCAAGUUAACAUGUAUGUGUGGAUCUGUUUCUAGGUUGUCUGUUCAGCCCCACUGAUUUACUUGUCUGUCAUGCGAGAGUGCCAUACUUUCUUAAUUACUGUAGCUUUAUAUCUUAGAAUCAGCUUGUCAAGUUCCAUGAAAAACAUUUUGAUUGGAAUUGCUUUGAAUCUGUUAAUCAGUUUGGAGAGACUAAAACAUUUUGUGUCUCUUUCCAAUAAUAUGGUAUGACUCUCUUAAGUUUUCUUUAAUGUCUUUCAAUAAAAUUUUAUAAUUUUUUUCCAUUAAA